AGCCAGGCCACUCAUCAGAGUCCGGGAGCCACUGGCAGAGAGGGCACGGCCCCACACUGCCCCAGAGACAUAUAGGAGCCAGGCAAACACCAGGGCGAGUGAGCUCGGGCCAUCUGCUGCCUGCCUGUGGAAGGAGCGCUCGCCAGCCUCACCCAGCCCGAGAAGGUCCACCUCUGCCUCCGCCGGAGCUGCCCUCAUUCUGGCUCCAGUAAGUGCUGCUUCUUCCUCCUGGGUUUUUUUCCACUACCCUAUUCAGUAACCAGGCCACUCCUGUCCCUGUGGGAAACUCUUGCUGCCAGGAACUCCCAGCUGUCUGCUCUCCUGGGCAAAAAAGUUCCUUCUUCCUGAGCCCUCCUCUCACCAUCCAAGAUGUGGUCAAAGGUCUGUGCUGAGUGGAAACCCUGAGGCCUCUGCUCCUAGGGGAGCCUCCCCAGCUGCUGGCACUCACUGCCCCAGCAGGGACCACAUGCACCCUGGCUGCUCCUGAACACCUGUCUGCUGGCUCCCCUGGGCCCCAUGGAGACCUGGCGGAAAGGCUCCUUCCGCAACGCCUCCUUCUUCAAGCAGCUGAGCCUGGGGCGGCCACGGCGGCUCCGGCGACAGAGUAGUGUGCUUAGCCAGGCCAGCACAGCAGGUGGGGACCACGAGGAGUACAGCAACCGAGAAGUCAUCCGGGAGCUACAAGGGAGGCCAGAUGGCCGGCGCCUGCCACUGUGGGGGGACGAGCAGCCCCGGGCCACCCUGCUGGCCCCACCCAAGCCCCCACGCCUCUACCGAGAGAGCUCAAGCUGCCCCAACAUCCUGGAGCCCCCACCUGCCUACACAGCAGCCUACUCUGCCACCCUGCCAUCGGCGCUCUCUCUGUCGAGUGCCCUCCACCAGCACUCAGAGAAGGGCCUUGUGGACACUCCCUGCUUCCAGAGGACACCUACCCCAGACCUCAGUGAUCCCUUCCUCUCCUUCAAAGUGGACCUGGGGAUUUCACUUCUUGAGGAAGUUCUGCAGAUGCUAAGGGAGCAGUUUCCUAGCGAGCCCAGCUUCUAAAUGGGGUGAGGGUGGGCAAAGCCGGGGUGACUGGAAGAUCCAGAGGCUGGGGAUUAAGGAAAGGACAGGGACAGGACUCCAGGCCCAUCGCUGGAGGGUUCAGGCAGGCAGAGCUUCUUCAUCCUGGGGGAGGAUUCCAGGAUAGGAAUCCAGGGCUCUGCCUGCUCUCUGGGUCCUGGACAGUCCUUCCAGGCACCCCAGAGUGGAGGGACAGAGGCAAUCUGGAAAUGUUGGGGGGGCGGCCCUUCCUGGCAGGACCCUGAAGAAAGCUGGCUAUGCCGGGAAAGGGAGGCUGUGCCGGGAAAGGGAGGCUCUGUGCGGCACUACAGGAACCAGGUAGAGGCUGGCAGAGCCAGAAGGUGGCACGGGGUCAGAUCAGGGAGUGGGAGGACACAGACUGAGCAGAAGAGAUGAGUGCCCCAUGCCAGCCUCUUUGGAAGCCACUGUCAACAGAGAGAGGUCACAGGACAAGCUUGGGUAAAGGCAGUCCAACCCAGGCAGAAGAGGAAAGUGGGAAGGCCCAGGAAGAAAGGGGAGAAGGCCUGACCCUGUCUAAUCUGGUGGCCACUCACUGCAUGACACUGAAUUGAAAUAAAUAAAAUUAACAGUUCAGUUCCUCAGCUGCACCGUUAUUCCAGAUUCCACAUUCCAAAUGCCCGGUGGCCACACAUGAUUAAUGGCUACCACACUGGUCAGUGCAGAAUGGACGUAAACAUCGCUGCACAAAGUUCUAAUGGACAGCGCUGUCUAGACCAUGGCCUGGAGCCACCAGCAAAGGGGAGGCGCAUACAGGGGCUGGCCACAUAGGAAGAGAUAGGUAGAGAUAGAGUAUAACUCAGGAAAAAGACCAGGCAAAUCCUUAGCAGAAAUGAGGACGUGGCUCAGUCUGCCAACACAGCUACCCGGAGCAAUCCCUGGUGAAGGAAGGCAGCUCUAGAGAAUGCCAGCCACAGGCACGCGCACGGCUUGCAAAGGGGUACUUUGGGGAAUUCCCAGAAUUACUAGUGAUGGGAGCCCUGGCAGGUUUCCUUCCUCGAAGAGAGGAGAACUGGAUCCAGGGAUGGGCAUUCAACAGCGAAGCGGCACAGCUGGUUUCCAGAACCGUCUCCCGGGAUUAGACAGUUCUGCCGCCUGAACCCUCCGACGAUGGGCCUGCCAACCAGGCCAAGCCCACUGGGUCAAAGCCACAGGCUGUGCUACGGCCCCACCCCAUGGCCUCACCAGAACACAGAAACCAGAGCCCAGCAGCACUGGCUGGGCCAUGUGUUGGUGGCCCCCCGGGACUCGCUAAGAGUAGCAAAGGGGAGAGGGAAGCUCUGACACACACCAUUUCUACGACCUAAAUCAGUGGCCUCCCUCUUUCCUCCUCUUGUGUAUAGGUACCGAGCUGUGGAUACAGGAGAGAAUGAAUAAAAUUCUAACACAA